CCUUUCUCUGCGCUCUCGCUCGCGCUCCCCAGCGCCCUCCUGCUCUCCCGGCCGCGGUCCCCUCGUCCGCGCCGCCCCGCCGCCGGCUCCGCUGCCGCCCCUGGCGACCAUGGCGCACCGGGGGCCCUCGCGCGCCUCGAAGGGCCCCGGCCCCACCGCCCGAGCCCCGAGCCCCGGGGCUCCGCCGCCGCCGCGCUCGCCGCGCUCGCGGCCGCUCCUGCUGCUGCUGCUGCUGCUGGGCGCCUGCGGGGCGGCGGGGCGCUCCCCUGAGCCCGGGCGCCUGGGUCCUCACGCCCAACUGACCCGGGUGCCGCGGAGCCCUCCCGCGGGGCGCGCGGAGCCCGGUGGCGGCGAGGACCGGCAGGCGCGCGGCACGGAGCCAGGCGCCCCGGGUCCGAGUCCCGGUCCCGCUCCUGGUCCCGGCGAGGACGGCGCCCCCGCCGCGGGCUACCGGCGCUGGGAGCGGGCGGCGCCGCUGGCCGGAGUGGCUUCGCGGGCGCAGGUCUCGCUCAUCAGCACGUCGUUCGUGCUCAAGGGGGACGCGACGCACAACCAGGCGAUGGUGCACUGGACGGGCGAGAACAGCAGCGUGAUCUUGAUCCUGACGAAGUACUACCACGCAGACAUGGGGAAGGUUCUGGAAAGUUCUCUGUGGCGGUCAUCAGAUUUCGGGACGUCCUACACCAAGCUCACCCUCCAGCCUGGUGUCACCACCGUCAUCGACAAUUUCUACAUCUGCCCGACCAACAAGAGGAAGGUCAUCCUUGUCAGCUCCUCACUCAGUGACCGGGACCAGAGCCUAUUCCUCAGCGCAGACGAAGGCGCCACCUUUCAGAAGCAGCCCAUUCCCUUCUUCGUGGAAACUCUGAUUUUCCACCCUAAGGAGGAGGACAAGGUCCUCGCCUACACAAAGGAGAGCAAGCUCUACGUGUCAUCUGACUUGGGGAAAAAGUGGACACUUCUGCAAGAGCGAGUGACCAAAGACCACGUGUUCUGGUCUGUGUCUGGGGUGGACGCUGACCCUGACUUGGUCCACGUGGAAGCCCAAGACCUCGGUGGAGAUUUUCGGUACGUCACCUGCGCAAUCCACAAUUGCUCCGAGAAGAUGCUGACAGCCCCAUUCGCAGGCCCCAUUGACCACGGGUCUCUGACCGUGCAGGACGAUUACAUCUUCUUUAAGGCAACAUCAGCAAACCAGACAAAAUACUACGUCUCUUAUCGUCGAAAUGAAUUUGUCCUGAUGAAGCUGCCGAAGUAUGCAUUGCCAAAGGAUCUGCAGAUCAUCAGCACGGACGAGAGUCAGGUGUUCGUGGCGGUGCAGGAGUGGUACCAGAUGGACACCUACAACCUGUACCAGUCGGACCCACGGGGCGUGCGCUACGCGCUGGUGCUGCAGGACGUGCGCAGCUCACGGCAGGCGGAGGAGAGCGUGCUCAUCGACAUCCUGGAGGUCAGAGGGGUGAAAGGAGUCUUCCUGGCAAACCAAAAAAUUGAUGGGAAAGUGAUGACGCUUAUAACCUACAACAAGGGCCGCGACUGGGAUUACCUGAGGCCACCCAGCAUGGACAUGAAUGGAAAACCAACCAACUGCAAGCCUCCAGACUGCCACCUGCACCUGCACCUGCGCUGGGCAGACAACCCCUACGUAUCAGGCACCGUGCACACCAAGGACACCGCCCCAGGCCUCAUCAUGGGUGCAGGUAACCUGGGCUCACAGCUGGUGGAAUAUAAAGAAGAAAUGUACAUCACGUCAGACUGUGGUCACACCUGGCGGCAGGUGUUUGAGGAAGAGCAUCACAUCCUGUACCUGGACCACGGCGGCGUGAUCGUGGCCAUCAAAGACACCUCCAUCCCUUUGAAGAUCCUCAAGUUCAGUGUGGACGAGGGCCUCACCUGGAGCACGCACAACUUCACCAGCACCUCGGUGUUUGUGGACGGGCUGCUGAGUGAGCCAGGGGACGAGACGCUGGUCAUGACGGUCUUUGGCCACAUCAGCUUCCGCUCCGAUUGGGAGCUGGUCAAGGUGGACUUCCGGCCCUCAUUCUCCAGGCAGUGCGGCGAGGAGGACUACAGCUCCUGGGAGCUCUCCAACCUGCAGGGCGACCGCUGUAUCAUGGGCCAGCAGAGAAGUUUCCGGAAAAGAAAGUCCACGUCCUGGUGCAUCAAGGGGAGGAGCUUCACGUCGGCGCUCACGUCCCGCGUGUGCGAGUGCCGGGACUCGGACUUCCUGUGCGACUACGGAUUUGAGCGCUCCUCCUCCUCAGAGUCCAGCACCAACAAGUGCUCUGCCAACUUCUGGUUUAACCCAUUGUCCCCGCCUGACGACUGUGCCCUGGGCCAGACCUACACCAGCAGCCUUGGGUACCGGAAAGUGGUGUCCAACGUGUGUGAGGGUGGGGUGGACAUGCAGCAGAGUCAGGUGCAGCUGCAGUGCCCCCUCACGCCGCCCCGGGGCCUGCAGGUCAGCAUUCAAGGCGAGGCGGUGGCCGUGCGGCCUGGAGAGGACGUCCUGUUUGUGGUGCGGCAGGAGCAGGGUGAUGUCCUGACUACCAAGUACCAGGUAGACCUUGGGGACGGCUUCAAGGCCAUGUACGUGAACCUUACACUGACCGGGGAGCCCAUCCGGCACCGCUACGAGAGCCCCGGCAUCUACCGCGUGUCCGUCAGGGCAGAGAACACGGCAGGCCACGAUGAGGCGGUGCUCUUUGUCCAGGUCAACUCCCCCCUGCAGGCCCUCUACCUGGAGGUGGUUCCUGUCAUUGGCCUCAACCAGGAGGUGAACCUCACAGCUGUGCUGCUUCCCUUGAACCCUAACCUCACCGUCUUCUACUGGUGGAUCGGCCACAGCCUGCAGCCCCUCCUUUCCCUGGAUAAUUCUGUGACAACGCGGUUUUCGGACACGGGCGACGUGCGUGUGACGGUGCAGGCCGCCUGUGGGAACUCGGUGCUGCAGGACUCCAGGGUCCUCCGUGUGCUGGAUCAAUUUCAAGUCAUGCCUCUGCAGUUUUCCAAGGAGCUGGAUGCCUACAACCCCAACACCCCUGAGUGGAGGGAAGACGUGGGCCUGGUGGUCACCCGGCUGCUCUCCAAGGAGACCAGCGUCCCUCAGGAGCUUCUGGUGACUGUGGUGAAGCCGGGGCUGCCCACUUUGGCCGAUCUGUACGUGCUCCUGCCCCCUCCCAGGCCCACAAGGAAGAGGAGCCUCUCGAGUGAUAAGAGGCUCGCCGCCAUCCAGCAGGUGCUGAACGCACAGAAGAUCAGCUUCCUCCUGCGAGGCGGAGUCCGGGUCCUGGUGGCCCUGCGGGACACAGGCACAGGUGCUGAGCAGCUGGGCGGCGGUGGCGGCUACUGGGCGGUAGUGGUGCUGUUUGUCAUCGGGCUCUUCGCAGCGGGAGCCUUCAUCCUCUACAAGUUCAAAAGCAGGAAACGGCCAGGCAGGACCGUGUACGCCCAAAUGCACAACGAGAAGGAGCAGGAGAUGACCAGCCCUGUGAGUCACAGUGAGGACGUCCAGGGCGCUGUCCAGGCGCCCACUGCCAGGAGGGGGCGGAGCCUCAGCCCCUCUCGCACCCCCUUGCUGCCGAUGCCGGGGGCGAUCCCCACGCAGGCAACCACUCAGGCGUGGUCCUGAGCAUCAACUCCCGAGAGAUGCACAGCUACCUGGUGAGCUGAUGCCACCCCAGCAUCUGUCUUUUCACCCACGGAGGGCACAGAACCACCAGCAAAGCCGGCGGCUGGACUGGCGCCCCUCAGAGACCUGCGGAAAGCCCCCUCCCUGAGUCGUCGCCACACCAGGCGACAGGCACCACCCCCUCUGAUAAAUCCAAGCCCGCCCAGGCCCACGGGGGGCCCACGGGACCCCCCGGGACUCCCCGGACAUGGCCCUGCCCCUAUGGGACACCAGGCCUGACUCAGGCAGGUUCUGCCCCCCAGACCCCACACACGGCCGCCCCACGUGCUGUCGCUCAGCCCGAGGCCUGACUUCUCUGGGCUGAGGCUGGUCGUCCUGGAGCCCUCCCAGUACCUCGGGCUGCAAGAGCUGCAGACCCGUUCAGACACUGCGUUGCGGGCUCCUUCCCCGCAGAGGCCGGGGCCUCCCUGACUUUGCUUCUUCACUCCCACCUGUGCGGCCACCCAGUCCCUCUGUGGGAGCCCGGGUGCCAGGCCCUCCCAACACCACACCACCCUCCAGGCCCCCCUGCCCUCCGGCUGGAAACUGCAGCUCUGUAAAUGCCUCUCUAGGUAGCUGCUGGCGGUGGUGGGGGUGUCUCACUCUCUGUCUUUAUAGCCGGCGGUAGCCACCGGGGUGGCUCUGUCAGAGUUCCGUACUCGGGAGCCCCUUUCCCUGAGUGCCCAGGGUGUCUCCUCUGCCCAGAGGGGCAGCAGCUCUCCCUGGUUCUCCCCAGGGCAGACGGGGUAGGGCGGGCUCAGGACCCAGUGCCCAUGGUUCCUCACUCCUACCAGCAAGCAGCACCAUCCCGCAGGCUUCUCCCACCUGAUGGCUGUUCUCCCACCGGGUCUGGGCUCUGGAAGGAGCCAGAUGCCCCCAGAAAGGUGGGUGGUGGAGACGGCACCAGAUGUACCAGUUUUCUGCAGUUCCUUAUAGGCGAAGGGAACCGGGUGGAAACCAAGCUGGGAGAGGCUGAGGAUGGCAGGGCUGGAAGGGCCAUCAGCGUGACCCUCAUUUUCAAGAAGGGGAAACUGAGGCCCAGGGAGGAGAGUAACUGAAGGUCACAGCACGGUCACAGCAGAGGUGGCCGAACCCAGCCCUCUGCGCGCCAGUGCUGUGCGGUCUCCACACCCUUACGGUUUCCUAGAAUCAGGGAUGUUAGUGUAAGUCUAUAGGAAUAUAGGGGGGUGGGGGGGUCACCUUUUGCCUUGAAAUGGGAAGUCAGUAGCCCCUUCCUCCUCCUCCCUCCUCCCCCUCCUCUCUGGCAGGGAUCUCAGAUGACCGUGGCCUCCCUCUCAGAGGGGGAGAACGCCAGAGCCCUGGCUGGUGAUGUGCUGGCUGGGGGUGAAUCCCAAUGAGGGUCCCUCUCAGAGCGGGAGAACGCCAGAGCCCUGGAUGGUGAUGCGCUGGCUGGGGGUGAAUCCCAAUGAGGGUCCCUCUCAGAAAGGGAGAACGCCAGAGCCCUGGCUGGUGACAUGCUGGCUGGGGGUGAAUCCGAAUGACAGUGCAGACGUUCUCCCAUCCACCAUGUCUGAGCUUGGGGGAAUUGCCUCAUUUCCCCUGGAAAAGAAACAUGGUCCAUUAGAGGGGAAAGCCCAGGGGUGAAUCUUCACGCCCCAAACAGUGCCCGGUGGGGAGGAGGCACCCGCUCCUUGUUGAGUAAAACCACCCAUGGAGACUGGAACCUCAUCUCCCUGGGUCGGGGGGUGUUCAAGGCCACAGGACAAGGGGAGCACCCUGGGCCACACAGGCGUGGAGGUGUCCCCACCCCUUCCACCUGUCCCCCAGACCCAAAGCUCUCUCCCCACCCUACCUGCCCACCUGGGGCUCCUGUGCCCCCUCCCCACUCCAGAGGCCACCCUACAAGUUGUCCUCAAGGUCAUCCUGGAGAUGGGAUCCAGGACGUGGGGCCAUGACUCUCUGGGACCUUGCCACAGCCCCCAUUCCCCUGCUUGCAGUCUGCAAGGACACCUUUGCAGGGAUUCUUGUCCUGCUGGCCACCCCACCCACACCUGUCCCUGGCCAGCAGGCCGCCUGCAAGCGUCAGGCACACAGGGACAGACAUGGCGAGCACAGUGCAGGCCCGGGGCCCACGGGCAACAUGGAACCCUGGGAACUGCCCUCCCCCUUAGCUCACAGUGCCUGCGGUAGCCACUCUAGGUCGUUGGCCUUCCUUGACCACUCCAUUUAAUUCUCUCUGCUGUUUGGGUUGGGUUUUUCCCCUUAGUUAUCUGUGGGUUUCCUGUAUUUUAUGUUAAUAUUUCUAUUAAGAACAUGUUGGGCAUGUGGACCCAAGCACCUGGGAAGGAGGUGGCAUCUGAGACAGCCUGAUACGUUCCCGUCUGUGCACCCAUGGAGAUCCAGGCGUGGGCCCGUGUCUGUCCCUGGUUGUAAAUUCGAGGGUCUGCAUAUCUGAUGUUCAGGUAGACCUGGGCGCCUGGGAACGAGGCCAUCAGCUGCCAUGCACAUAACAAAGAGACAAUGCAUUCCUUCUUAUUUUUCCUUUUUAAAAAUCGAUGAAUCAUUUGUGAUGCUUUUAACAAAGAUUAAAUGAAUUUGAUCAGC